GAUUCUAUGGAACCUUUUUGUAGGGAGAAGGGCAGGAUGUUUUUAACUGAAUGUGACCUCAGGGGAAUACUAGAGGUAAGGAGAGAAAAAUAAUUGAGGUAACUGUGGGUGUUUUACAUCUCGGAAACCAUGGCUUUUAAUAAGGCCACAUGAAGAGAGAAGCUGGCAUCAUCCCACGCAAAAACCAGUGCCUGGCAGAGUUGUGGAAGAAAAUAAUAAAAUUUCUGAAUGGGGCAGCGUGGAGAAAUCCUAAGAGAAAUAGCAUAAGAGCAUUUUGGAACACAUCCAGGAAAAGAUAACUUUCGACACACCUGUAGACGUUCGCCAGGUAAAGAGCCCCCAAUUUUGUGAGUGUCCCUGAAGCAUUGUGACAAUUCCAUUUUAUGUGUCUGCGUGCUCAUAUCAAGACUAAGGAGUGAUGGAAACUCUCCAGUUCAGAUCCAGUAGCUUUUAGGGAAGGGACUGGAAGGACAAAUACAAAUACUGUUAUGCCUACUAGUGAACUACAGUUGCUGACUUAAGUUGAAGAAGCAUCUAUUUAAUGUCUGGUCAAAUCCUACAAGAAACACAGAAAUCUAUGAUUAAAAAGCUGAGCACUUUGAUAUACUGCAAAGGGUAGAGAAGGCAGGACGGUAGAAAUUUUCUGCAAGAAAGAAUGAAUUUCAGGAUUUAUCACUAAAUAAGACAAAGUCAUUUAUUUAGUCCCCCUGACACAGCAGGGCAAACUGAGUUGACAUACAAGUUACCUGGAGAAAAAGAGAGCAAUUCCAGGACUUCCUCUUCAGCCUAAAAGAAGGUACCAGAUCUGUGCACUGGGGCGAUGUGGAAGAGACCUGCUUAUUGCCCCUGAUGUAAGCUCCAGUAAGAAAAGACGUCAAGUACAAGUACUAGGAAAUCACUUUAUACAUCUGUUUAUAGAUGGAUGCAGAGGCUGAAGAUAAAACGCUGCGUACUCGCUCUAAAGGAACCGAGGUGCCAAUGGAUUCACUAAUCCAGGAGCUCAGUGUUGCCUAUGAUUGCUCCAUGGCAAAGAAGAGAACAGCUGAAGAUCAGGCUUUGGGGGUUCCAGUCAACAAAAGGAAAUCCCUGCUAAUGAAGCCCCGACACUACAGCCCAAAAGCAGACUGCCAAGAAGACCGCAGUGACAGGACAGAGGACGAUGGCCCCUUGGAAACACAUGGUCACUCUACCGCAGAGGAAAUCAUGAUAAAACCUAUGGAUGAAAGUCUUCUUUCAACUGCACAAGAAAACUCCAGUAGGAAGGAAGACAGAUACUCUUGUUAUCAAGAGCUCAUGGUCAAGUCUUUAAUGCACUUGGGGAAAUUUGAAAAAAAUGUAUCUGUUCAGACUGUAAGUGAAAAUUUAAAUGACAGUGGCAUCCAGUCUUUAAAAGCAGAGAGCGAUGAAGCAGACGAGUGCUUUCUGAUUCAUUCUGAUGAUGGAAGAGACAAGAUUGAUGAUUCUCAGCCACCCUUCUGCUCCUCUGAUGACAAUGAAAGUAACUCUGAAAGUGCAGAAAAUGGCUGGGACAGUGGCUCCAACUUCUCAGAAGAAACCAAACCACCUAGAGUCCCAAAGUAUGUUUUAACAGAUCAUAAAAAAGACCUAUUGGAAGUUCCUGAAAUAAAAACUGAAGGUGACAAAUUUAUCCCUUGUGAGAACAGGUGUGAUUCUGAAACAGAAAGGAAAGACCCGCAGAAUGCUCUCGCAGAACCCCUGGAUGGCAAUGCCCAGCCCUCAUUCCCUGACGUUGAGGAGGAAGAUAGCGAGAGCCUGGCAGUAAUGACGGAAGAGGGUAGUGACCUGGAAAAGGCCAAGGGGAAUUUAAGUUUGCUGGAGCAGGCAAUUGCUCUGCAGGCUGAGCGAGGUUGUGUUUUCCAUAACACCUACAAAGAGCUGGAUAGGUUCCUGCUGGAGCACCUAGCAGGGGAAAGGAGGCAAACCAAAGUUAUCGACAUGGGUGGAAGACAAAUCUUUAACAAUAAACAUUCACCAAGGCCUGAAAAGAGGGAGACCAAGUGCCCGAUCCCUGGAUGUGAUGGCACGGGACACGUGACAGGGCUCUACCCGCACCACCGCAGCCUUUCGGGGUGCCCCCACAAAGUGCGGGUUCCCCUGGAAAUUCUUGCCAUGCAUGAAAAUGUGCUCAAGUGUCCCACGCCGGGAUGCACAGGAAGGGGUCAUGUGAACAGCAACCGCAACACCCACAGGAGUCUUUCUGGUUGUCCAAUUGCUGCAGCUGAAAAAUUGGCAAUGUCCCAGGAUAAAAAUCAGCUUGAUUCUCCCCAAACUGGGCAGUGUCCUGACCAGGCCCACAGGACAAGUUUGGUGAAGCAAAUUGAAUUCAAUUUCCCGUCACAAGCCAUCACCUCUCCCAGAGCCACAGUGUCAAAAGAACAAGAGAAGUUUGGAAAAGUACCAUUUGAUUAUGCCAGUUUUGAUGCCCAAGUUUUCGGUAAACGCCCUCUCAUACAAACAGUGCAAGGACGAAAAACACCACCAUUUCCUGAAUCAAAGCAUUUUCCAAAUCCAGUGAAAUUUCCUAAUCGACUGCCUAGUGCAGGCGCCCACACCCAGAGCCCUGGCCGUGCCAGCUCUUAUAGCUACGGUCAAUGUAGUGAAGACACCCACAUAGCAGCAGCUGCUGCCAUCCUGAACCUUUCCACCCGCUGCAGGGAAGCCACAGACAUCCUCUCCAACAAGCCACAGAGUCUGCAUGCCAAGGGAGCCGAAAUAGAAGUGGAUGAAAAUGGCACAUUGGACUUAAGCAUGAAAAAAAAUCGAAUCCUGGACAAGUCUGCACCCCUAACUUCCUCUAACACUUCUAUUCCAACUCCUUCCUCUUCCCCAUUCAAAACAAGCAGCAUUCUGGUCAAUGCAGCAUUCUAUCAGGCUCUUUGUGACCAAGAGGGCUGGGACACUCCUAUCAACUAUAGCAAAACUCACGGGAAGACAGAGGAGGAGAAAGAGAAAGACCCAGUGAGCUCUCUAGAAAAUUUAGAGGAAAAAAAGUUUCCUGGAGAGGCCUCUAUACCAAGCCCUAAACCCAAGCUUCAUGCAAGAGAUCUCAAAAAGGAACUAAUCACCUGUCCAACACCAGGAUGUGAUGGAAGUGGCCACGUGACAGGAAACUAUGCAUCUCAUCGCAGUGUUUCUGGAUGUCCUUUAGCAGAUAAGACUCUAAAAUCCCUCAUGGCUGCCAACUCUCAGGAGCUUAAGUGUCCAACCCCAGGCUGCGAUGGCUCGGGGCACGUGACUGGAAACUAUGCUUCCCACAGAAGCUUGUCCGGAUGCCCUCGUGCAAGGAAAGGUGGUGUCAAAAUGACCCCUACCAAGGAAGAAAAAGAAGACCCUGAACUGAAAUGUCCUGUGAUAGGGUGUGAUGGCCAAGGUCACAUAUCAGGUAAAUACACAUCACACCGCACAGCUUCUGGCUGUCCUCUGGCUGCCAAGAGACAGAAGGAGAAUCCUCUCAAUGGAGCCUCCCUCUCCUGGAAACUGAACAAACAAGAGCUACCACAUUGUCCCUUGCCAGGCUGCAAUGGGCUGGGCCAUGUAAAUAAUGUUUUUGUCACCCACCGAAGCUUAUCUGGAUGUCCUCUCAAUGCACAAGUUAUCAAAAAGGGCAAGGUUUCUGAAGAACUCAUGACCAUCAAGCUCAAAGCAACUGGGGGAAUAGAGAGUGAUGAAGAAAUUAGGCAUUUGGAUGAAGAAAUAAAGGAACUGAAUGAAUCCAACCUUAAAAUUGAAGCAGAUAUGAUGAAACUUCAGACCCAGAUCACAUCUAUGGAGAGCAACUUAAAGACGAUAGAGGAGGAGAACAAACUCAUAGAACAGAACAAUGAAAGUCUGCUGAAAGAGCUGGCAGGUCUAAGCCAAGCUCUCAUUUCAAGCCUUGCUGACAUCCAGCUUCCACAGAUGGGACCUAUCAGUGAGCAGAAUUUUGAAGCAUAUGUAAAUACACUCACAGAUAUGUACAGCAAUCUGGAACGGGACUAUUCCCCGGAAUGCAAAGCUCUACUGGAAAGUAUCAAACAGGCAGUGAAGGGUAUCCAUGUGUAGGAUCACAGCGCUGCCGGGCAACAGAAGUUACCAACAGCAGUAAACUCCAGAUGGAUCUGUUAGAGGUUCAUGUACUGCUAAGGCGUGGAGGUUGCCGUACUGCAUUUACAAUUUGCAACAUUGCACUAAUUUUAUUUUCCCCAGCUGAUAUAAAAAGGAAAGAAAAACUAUGAUAGACUUCUUGGAUUAAAAGCAAUGCAGUCAAUUAUUAGAUCUUAUUUAUUUUCAUAUGUUUUUCUUUUAUUUCUUCAUUGUACUCUUUUUUUUUUUGUAAAGUAUAUGUAAAAUAAAUGUGACAUUUUUAUAAUUUAUUUAUUACUAAUCAAAGAGUUUUUUAUCUUUUAACUGCAUUUUGAAGUCUGCCGUAUUUUUACAAGUGUGUUUAUUAAUUUAUUUUCCAAUAGGAUUUAAAUAGAAAUGCUAUUCUCAAGUCAUCUUUCUUGCUGGGUUUUAAUGAGGAAACAGGAAAGGGUGAAGGAAAUCCUUGUCUAAGGACUGCACUAUAGUUGAGUUUGAUUUUUAUUGCACACUUCUUCCCCCACCUUUCACUGAUUUUUGUAUUUAUAAAUGAAUUUGCGGUAAGGUGAGCUGCACGGAAGGAAUAAGAAGACAAAUGGCGCCCACUAGUGGGGAAUCCGCACUCACAAAAGCACAGGAUGCUGGAAAACAGCCUGCUCAGAAUUUGUUAGCAAUAAUUAAAUAUAGCAAUCAGCAAAGUAUUCGACUUGGCUGGACGGUUUUCGUUAAUAUGAAUUAUUUAUUUGAAAUGUUUUAAAGAAACAUAAGCCUUUUUAGUGAUGCAGAUUUGUCUGUUUGUUUUUCAAGUCAUAUCAGAUCGUUGGCAACUCGUAUCCCAAGAUGAAAAAUAAGACUUGGUGUGACCAGCCAGGCUUUCCUGCCAUAUGUUGGUACAAUAUACAAGUGACAAUAUUGGUGUAGAUUUGUACUUAGCAAAUACAAACACAUCCAAAUGAAAAAUUUUGUAGAUACCAUAUCCCCUGAAAUAGCAUUUAUCUUACUGGGUUGACUGGAAAGGAAUGGAAAAUAUAGUAACACAUGAAAAAAUGCUACUCCAAUCUGAAUGAUUACUUCAAACACUGGCACCUUGGGUCUCACCCACCAUAGGAAACAAGACAACAUUCAAUUUGAUAGAAAUCUUGCCACAAAACUUCAAAUGCUACAAAAUAUACACACACACUCACACACACAGGCAUACUCACACACAGACACACACACACACACACACACAGACUCAUCCACACUUCAAAUUGAGCCCACAAUCUUGAAUUUCUGAACGGAUCAGAGUUUCAUAGUUUCUAUAGUAAAGGCAAUGUCUAUUUCAGGGAUUGUAAAGUAGUUAAGCAUUGUUUCAAAAGUUUUUUUAUAUUUAUUUUUUUUAAGGAAAAGGUAUAGACAACCAGCUAAACUGCCUUUUUGGUGUGCACACACAUUUCAUGUGCAGACGUGCCUCUGUGUAAAUGUACACAUGAACUUCAUGUGGGCUUAAUUUUCUGUGCUAUAAACAAAAGUGUUUAUUUUUUAUUAACCUCAUGGAUAUUUAGAUGGAAAGUGAUGGCAUUCACAGGCUUGAUGUAUUCCACUGUUAUUACUGUUACCUGCACAAAUGAAAAACAAUACUCAACAGUAAUUCCACUCCCAUGAAACUUUGGUCAUUGUUAUGCAUUAAGUGGGGCUUAUCUUUGGUUUGGAGUUCAUUUGAACUCUUGAACCUUAGUUUAGUGAAGAUGAACUGUCUGUUCUUAGGUAGAAACGGUGUUUAUUUAAAAAUCAGUUUUAAAAAAUGAGCUACCAUAUGUGCUGUCUAUUAUAAAUGGGACACCAAACAAAAUUUUCUAUUACAGUUGUGUACUUGCAAACAUUUUGCUAUACAGUACUUCAUAGAUGCAUACAAAUGAGCUCACUUAUUACAAAGACAAACGUUUAAUUUGCUAAAUAUUUUAACAAGUUUGUUAUAUAUUUUAUUUAAUUUAAAAGAAAUCUCUUACCAACCUACAUAUUUAUUACUAUAAUUUGCUAUGACUUCAGGUUAAUUUAUUUGUGUUUGCAUAGUUUGAGCAGGAUGUUUUGUGAAGUAUGUUUGUAUUUAUUUGCCUACUUUGUACUUGAUGUGUUUUGUAAUGUGCACUGAAUUUGUUUUCUUUUCAACUAUGUUAAUGAUCAAUACUGUAAAUUGGGUCUUUUGUAAACAAAAAGGCAAUGAUGUAUGCAUUUUUUUUAAUUUGAGGUAGUUUGUUUGUAUACUGUUUCUCCAAACACUUAAUAUUUCUUACAUCAAAGCAACAAAAUUGUGUUCAGUGCUGUACAUUUGGUGUAUGGUAGGAAAUAAAAAUUGAUAACGA